AAUUCUCCCGGUGGCUCGACUCGGCUCGCAGGCUUCGGAGAAACCCCUACUCCAGUCGCCGACUCAGCGCCCAAGAGGGUCGCCUUGGGCUGGGGGCGCACCCCAGGGAGGGGAGGGGUCCAGGCAGCUGGGCCGCCGCGGACACCUAGCGGCUUCAGGGUGAACCCCGACCGCAGCCGUCGCCGCCUCGGGCAGAGUUUGCGCCCUUGCUUUGCGCCCCGGGCGCUGAAGCCGGGCGGGCGAUGCCCGCGGCGUGAAAGCGCCCGCGGCGGGCGCCGACCUCUGUCCUAGUCUCCUGCUCCCCCCGCCCCGCUUGUCCCGUGCCCUUGUGACCCUGGCUUUGGCGCCGUCGCCCAGGCGCCCCGCAAUGUAGCUGCCCCUGCGCCUCGGCGGGAGGCGUCCUGCCCCGCGAGCGCCCGGGGCCCGGAGCCCGGCCUGGGGGCUCAGCCGAGCUCGGGCGGGGCCGGGGCCGCGGUGGCGAUGCACCGGGCCCGUUAGCGCCAGGAGCGCCAGGCAGCUGAGGCGGGGGGCAAGCCCUCCCUCGGAGGAGCCGCGCCCCCGGCCCCGCCGGUCCCGCCGCGAUGCUGUUCCACAGUCUGUCGGGCCCCGAGGUGCACGGGGUCAUCGACGAGAUGGACCGCAGGGCCAAGAGCGAGGCUCCCGCCAUCAGCUCCGCCAUCGACCGCGGCGACACCGAGACGACCAUGCCGUCCAUCAGCAGUGACCGCGCCGCGCUGUGCGCCGGCUGCGGGGGCAAGAUCUCGGACCGCUACUACCUGCUGGCGGUGGACAAGCAGUGGCACAUGCGCUGCCUCAAGUGCUGCGAGUGCAAGCUCAACCUGGAGUCGGAGCUCACCUGUUUCAGCAAGGACGGUAGCAUCUACUGCAAGGAAGACUACUACAGGCGCUUCUCUGUGCAGCGCUGCGCCCGCUGCCACCUGGGCAUCUCGGCCUCGGAGAUGGUGAUGCGCGCUCGGGACUUGGUUUAUCACCUCAACUGCUUCACGUGCACCACGUGUAACAAGAUGCUGACCACGGGCGACCACUUCGGCAUGAAGGACAGCCUGGUCUACUGCCGCUUGCACUUCGAGGCGCUGCUGCAGGGCGAGUACCCCGCACACUUCAACCAUGCCGACGUGGCAGCGGCGGCCGCUGCAGCCGCGGCGGCCAAGAGCGCGGGGCUGGGCGCAGCAGGGGCCAACCCUCUGGGUCUUCCCUACUACAAUGGCGUGGGCACUGUGCAGAAGGGGCGGCCGAGGAAACGUAAGAGCCCGGGCCCCGGUGCGGAUCUGGCGGCCUACAACGCUGCGCUAAGCUGCAACGAAAACGACGCAGAGCACCUGGACCGUGACCAGCCAUACCCGAGCAGCCAGAAGACCAAGCGCAUGCGCACGUCCUUCAAGCACCACCAGCUUCGGACCAUGAAGUCUUACUUUGCCAUUAACCACAACCCCGACGCCAAGGACUUGAAGCAGCUCGCGCAAAAGACGGGCCUCACCAAGCGGGUCCUCCAGGCAUCUCUCUAGAUUUAUCUUCUGCCUCCCAGACUCUCCUGGAAGCAAGGUCUGGUUCCAGAACGCCCGAGCCAAGUUCAGGCGCAACCUCUUACGGCAGGAAAACACGGGCGUGGACAAGUCGACAGACGCGGCGCUGCAGACAGGGACGCCAUCGGGCCCGGCCUCGGAGCUCUCCAACGCCUCGCUCAGCCCCUCCAGCACGCCCACCACCCUGACAGACUUGACUAGCCCCACCCUGCCAACUGUGACGUCCGUCUUAACUUCUGUGCCUGGCAACCUGGAGGGCCAUGAGCCUCACAGCCCCUCACAAACGACUCUUACCAACCUUUUCUAAUGACUCGCAACCCCUCACCCCACAAUUUCUUUAAAAAAGAAAUUAUCUUUAGUUGAAUUCCAAGUGUAUUUUAAAAUAGAGGCUUUGAGCAACUAACUAACCACAUUUUAGGAUCUCGCCUGGAAACAGAGGUAAAAAAAAGAAGUGUGCGCCCGGCUAAUGCAGCGGUGUGGACCGAGGAACAACUUGGAAGAUCUACCUGCAACACAACAUUUGUGUCACUGUACAGUUUUGUGGACUGAGCGAGGAAAAACAACAAAUAAUUUAAGUUGGCUAGAGCUUCUGUAUUUUCAAAGACUGCCACGUGCCUUAGGAAUACUGUUUUAUCUCCAUACUUUGGAUGACUUGUUCAUUUUUCUCUCCCUCUUUUUCUCUGUAUAUUUAUGACCAGAGCAAAAAUGUAAAAAACAAAAAAAACAACAAAAAAAGUUUGUUACUUUGAAUAGUCCUAAAAAGAAAAAAAGAAAAAAAAAAAAGGAAAAAUCAAACCCCCUCCAACGGUCGCUUUGUUGUUUUAGAAUUUUAAGGUGGAAGUCUGUUCGAAUAUCAGAAUUUGUAAAAUCUAACCAGUAAUAAAACCACUUAUUGAAACUA